CUCUGCGCGUAAUGGCAGCGCCGUGGCCUCGCGUCCAUCUUUGCCGUUCUCUCGGACCUGUCACAAAGGAGUCGCGCCGCCGCCGCCGCCCCCUCCCUCCGGUGGGCCCGGGAGGUAGAGAAAGUCAGUGCCACAGCCCGACCGCGCUGCUCUGAGCCCUGGGCACGCGGAACGGGAGGGAGUCUGAGGGUUGGGGACGUCUGUGAGGGAGGGGAACAGCCGCUCGAGCCUGGGGCGGGCGGACCGGACUGGGGCCGGGGUAGGCUCUGGAAAGGGCCCGGGAGAGAGGUGGCGUUGGUCAGAACCUGAGAAACAGCCGAGAGGUUUUCCACCGAGGCCCGCGCUUGAGGGAUCUGAAGAGGUUCCUAGAAGAGGGUGUUCCCUCUUUCGGGGGUCCUCACCAGAAGAGGUUCUUGGGGGUCGCCCUUCUGAGGAGGCUGCGGCUAACAGGGCCCAGGUGAGAGGCAGCUAUCUAUCUCCUGGGGUGGCUCCUGGUACCGAUGGGGUCCUGACCUACUCAGGGGUGCCCGGGAUAGAAAGGGUAGAUGAAGGGACGCUUUAGGAGGGUUCUUUUUGUGGAGUUUACGGUCUAGGUGGCACGGAUGAGGCAUACCUCCCCGGGGAGAUUUAGAAACGCCUUGGGAUAGAGAGAGAAUGGGGCUAGGAAGCAGGAGCUAGAACUAGCGGAAUGUCCUACUACGGAAGCCGGAGCUGAAAAUUGGAGGGAAACUAUGAACACCAAAUAAAAACUGCCAUUGGAUGUCCAGAAUCCCCUGUAGUUGAUAAUGUUGGGAAUAAGCUCUGCAACUUUCUUUGGCAUUCAGUUGUUAAAAACAAAUAGGAUGCAAAUUCCUCAACUCCAGGUUAUGAAAACAGUACUUGGAAAACUGAAAACUACCUAAAUGAUCGUCUUUGGUUGGGCCGUGUUCUUAGCGAGCAGAAGCCUUGGCCAGGGUCUGUUGUUGACUCUCGAAGAGCACAUAGCCCACUUCCUAGGGACUGGAGGUGCCGCUACUACCAUGGGUAAUUCCUGUAUCUGCCGAGAUGACAGUGGAACAGAUGACAGUGUUGACACCCAACAGCAACAGGCCGAGAACAGUGCAGUACCCACUGCUGACACAAGGAGCCAACCACGGGACCCUGUUCGGCCACCAAGGAGGGGCCGAGGACCUCAUGAGCCAAGGAGAAAGAAACAAAAUGUGGAUGGGCUAGUGUUGGACACACUGGCAGUAAUACGGACUCUUGUAGAUAAAAGAAAACUUCAAAAUGAAGAUGCGUAUAUAGGCCCUUGCUUCCAUAAGUCCUCAACCGGGAUUGUCGUCUCUCUUCCUGGCAUUUCUCUGAGUGAUCAGGAACCUCCCUAUUCAAUGAUAACAUUACACGAAAUGGCAGAAACAGAUGAAGGAUGGUUGGAUGUUGUCCAGUCUUUAAUUAGAGUUAUUCCACUGGAAGAUCCACUGGGACCAGCUGUUAUAACAUUGUUACUAGAUGAAUGUCCAUUGCCCACUAAAGAUGCACUCCAGAAAUUGACUGAAAUUCUCAAUUUAAAUGGAGAAGUAGCUUGCCAGGACUCAAGCCAUCCUGCCAAACACAGGAACACAUCUGCAGUCCUAGGCUGCUUGGCCGAGAAACUAGCAGGUCCUGCAAGUAUAGGUUUACUUAGCCCAGGAAUACUGGAAUACUUGCUACAGUGUCUGAAGUUACAGUCCCACCCCACAGUCAUGCUUUUUGCACUUAUCGCACUGGAAAAGUUUGCACAGACAAGUGAAAAUAAAUUGACUAUUUCUGAAUCCAGUAUUAGUGACCGGCUUGUCACAUUGGAGUCCUGGGCUAAUGAUCCUGAUUAUCUGAAACGUCAAGUUGGUUUCUGUGCCCAGUGGAGCUUAGACAAUCUCUUUUUAAAAGAAGGUAGACAGCUGACCUAUGAGAAAGUGAACUUGAGUAGCAUUAGGGCCAUGCUGAAUAGCAAUGAUGUCAGCGAGUACCUGAAGAUCUCACCUCAUGGCUUAGAGGCUCGCUGUGAUGCCUCCUCUUUUGAAAGUGUGCGUUGCACCUUUUGUGUGGAUGCCGGGGUAUGGUACUAUGAAGUAACAGUGGUCACUUCUGGCGUCAUGCAGAUUGGCUGGGCCACUCGAGACAGCAAAUUCCUCAAUCAUGAAGGCUACGGCAUUGGGGAUGAUGAAUACUCCUGUGCGUAUGAUGGCUGCCGGCAGCUGAUUUGGUACAAUGCCAGAAGUAAGCCUCACAUACACCCAUGCUGGAAAGAAGGAGAUACAGUAGGAUUUCUGUUAGACUUGAAUGAAAAGCAAAUGAUCUUCUUUUUAAAUGGCAACCAGCUGCCUCCUGAAAAGCAAGUCUUUUCAUCUACUGUAUCUGGAUUUUUUGCUGCAGCUAGUUUCAUGUCAUAUCAACAAUGUGAGUUCAAUUUUGGAGCAAAACCAUUCAAAUACCCACCAUCUAUGAAAUUUAGCACUUUUAAUGACUACGCCUUCCUAACAGCUGAAGAAAAAAUCAUUUUGCCAAGGCACAGGCGUCUUGCUCUGUUGAAGCAAGUCAGUAUCCGAGAAAACUGCUGUUCCCUUUGUUGUGAUGAGGUAGCAGACACACAAUUGAAGCCAUGUGGACACAGUGACCUGUGCAUGGAUUGUGCCUUGCAGCUGGAGACCUGCCCAUUGUGUCGUAAAGAAAUAGUAUCUAGAAUCAGACAGAUUUCUCAUAUUUCAUGACACAUGUGAAGAGGCAUCGUGGACUUUUUUCUACUCAAUUCCAGCCAAUGUUGAAAAGAAAAAGAAAAAAAAAACUCUCUAAUCAGUUGUACACACAUUGAAACUUAUAGCCAUGGCCAGAUUUUAUGCUAAAAAUGGUAGUUUGUCAAAGACAAAAUUCUCUUAGAAUCUAAUCCAACUUGCCAGCCCUGAGAAAAUCCCUUUUAAGGCCAAGGAAAGCUGAAUGCUAGCAGCCAGGCCUGUGGUACUUCCAUGAGAAACCAUAGCAGACAAUGCCCUCCCAAGUACUGAAAUCACACUGGAAUCCCCCUUGUUGGGUUCAUUUGAUUGUUUAACACAGGAUGUGUUGUGUCAUUCUGAAGUUUUUAUUUGGGGCAGAAGUCUUUAUGGAGAUGUAAAUGACAGCGUUUCUGGGUUAUGCAUAACUUCUCACUGGUCAGAGACACCGGUGUGUCAAGCAUGGAUAUUGCAUUGCAAGACUUGAAUCUAUAAAAAUUAGAAUCACACAGUCAGUACUACAAGCAAAACAGAGAACCUGAAAGAAGGUGCACAGACUGUAAGAAAAAACCCAAGUUUGUGAUAUUUCAGUGAUUCCAAAGAACAUUCUAGGUUUUUUGUUUGUUUUUUUGUUUUUUGGGUUUUUUUUUUUUACUGCAGAAAAUUGGUGGUAUUUUCACAUUCAUAGUGUUUCUAUCCAAUUUCAGUACCCACAUUUAAUGAGGAAAAAAUGUUUUACCAAUGAAGGAGGAAUUCUUAAAUUAGCUGUAAUGUUAGGUUGGAGAAAAUUUGGUAUUUAGGGUAUUUUCAAGGUACCAUCAAAUCAGAUUUCUGUUUUUUUGUUAAAAAAAAUUUUUUUAAUCAGUAUUGUUUUUACAAGUAAUAUACUUUGAAACUCUUGAACUAAUAGUCUCAAAAACUCUAGAGGACAGUCUGAGAACACGUAUUUCUAUUGUUCUAAAUAAAUACAUGUUUUUGAAUAGUUCAAUCAUGAAUUAUUGACUAUGUCUUCAUCAAAAGUGUUAAUCCCUCUCAGGGUCUCUGGUGAAGACCUUCAAGAGUUUGGUUUUUUCUCCCAGGAAAUUGGAAGGUAGAAUUGUAAAUUCAUAGAACUUCUUUUAUAAUGGUGUACCUCAGCAGCUGCCUUUCAAUUUAUGCCAAGUCCUUACAGAGUUUAUACUUGAAUAGUAAAUAUGUCUUCUGAGUUUUACAGUGUCUUAAACUCAAUGCACAUUUUUUUUUCUUCUUUUUCCACCCCUUCUUGUUUGUAGUUCAUUAUACCUGUCCUAUUACAGAACUGAUUUCCUUCCUGGCUGUACAUGUUGGGGUGCUGGAUUUUUUUCCGUGUCUUUAGUCUUCCAUAAAUCCACACACACACACACACACAAAAAAUAUAUAUAUAUAUAAAUAUAUAUGUAGGAUACAUGUUCUCUUCUUUAGCUUGUGGUGAAUACAGUAAUUUGCAUUGAAGAAUAAAACAUCUGUUGCCUUUUUUGA